CCGGGAGGACCCGCUUUUGUUCCGCGGAGCCGCUGGCCCGAGGCAGCUAUUGUCUUGCGCCCCUGGCUGGGCUGCGUCAGGCUGGGGCCAGGGCCGGGCGGGUGGCGGUGUGAGCGCGGUGCCCCCGGGUAUGCAGGGCGGGCCGCAGGGUCUCUGGAGCCCAUCCGCGGGGCCUGGGGGGGUCGGGACCCCUGGCAGUUUGACCCUCCUCUUGGCACCGGCCCGGACCGGAUGGACGCUUCUUGGCCAGCGCCCAGGACAGGUGCCUGGGGACACGGGUGGAGAGCCAGGGCCUUCCUGAGCGGCUUCUGUCUGUGCAGGAAGGAGGCUGAAGUCUGAAGAGGGAAGCCCGGGUAGGCCUUCUGCUCCCUGAGAGGGUUCCUCCUCUCCCCUCCACACCCCCUACGCCGGCUCUGACUCCCGGGACCUGCAAAGGAGCUUCCGGAGCUUUAAUGGAAGUCUUCUCUGCCUCCGAGGCGCACGUGAUGGGAGGGAUAGAGACAGGCCCUGCCCACUAAUGGAUGCUGGAGGAGAUCUCUAAGGAAAACGGGAUCCUCCCCCUCUCAGCAUUGAGGUGGGGGGAGGCAUAGGCAGUUUGUCCUCUGCUCAGAGCAGUGCUGGGUUCAGUAACAGGCAGGGAAACUGAGCAGAGGAGAGACCAGCCAAGACCCUCUGUGGUGGGAGGCAGGUCUCCCACACACCUGCUACCUGGGCAACUAGGCCCCUGCCUGUCCUACGGCCCUGGUGUGGCCCCCAGGGUCUGGCCCUCAGAGGUGGAGGGACCAGUUUUUGGGAAAUCCAUGGUCACAGUGUGUCUGAUGACCCCAAGCUGAGCUUGGGGAAGCUGAGGUGGAUGACAGUCAGCCCUGCUCUCCCACCCCAAGUUUGCUCCCCCAGCUUGGCUUUUUGGCAUCUCUGCCUGGGGCCACGCCCUGGCAGGUGCACUGCUGUGUGGAGAAGUAAGCUCCAGGUCUUGGAGACUGGUCAGAGGCUGUGGCACCAAGGGAAAGGGCAUUUUGUGGUGGCCAAGGGCUUGCUGCCUGGUGAGAGAUGCCAGCCUGGCUUGUCCUGGACUCUACCUGGGAGGGCCAUAAUGGGGAUGGAGAAGAUUCAUUCAUUCAUCCAUCGGACAGCAGCCACCUCCUGCCCUCUGGGAGCCUGGCCUGCAGGUGUGGGAUCCAGGUGUGCAAUCUCACCUUAACUCAUUCUCUGUGUGUGCUAGCCAGGCCUUGGACAGGGGAGGGGCCUGCCCCUGCAGUCUGUUCUUCAGGACACAGACCGUGGUGCAUCUGUGAAGUCCGGUGGUUUGGGUAGAUAAGUAAUAUGGGACCAGGGCCCAGCCACCUGUGCCCCAGCAUCCCUCUGUGUGUUGGUCCAAUCUUGCUUUUCUGCUCCCUGUGUUCCUUGCAUUUUGCCACAAAAGUGAGACUGAUGCUACCCAGCACGUCCCACGACCCCAGCCCCCUCUGUCCUUCUCACCUCCUUGUGAAGAAGCUGAGCCGAAGGUGCGUGAUGGGGCCCAGAGCCCCUAUGCUGGGCUCAGCCCUGUGUUCCCGGGACCCUCUUGUGAGCAGGGGUAGGUGGUCUACCUCCCUGGUCACUCUGGCCCCUCCCACAAGCCCAAGGGAGCUCAUGGGAAACCCCAGGCCUGGGCAGCAGCCUGUUUCUGGGCCAGUCCUGGGGGCCCCAGACCUGGUGCACCAGAGAUUGAAGAGCCAAGGGAGGGAUGAGUGCUGGGAGGCCGGGCGGGGUGCAAGAGGAGCAAGGAUGGGGCCCCAGCUGGGGAGGGGGUGAUGAGAGACGACUGACAGGAUGCAGCAUGUGGGAUUGGGCUGGAGGUGGGGUGUUCAGGGUAGAGCCCAUGUCUAGGGUACAGAGGGGAGCAGCCCAGAGUUGGGUCUGAGGCAGAGGCUGUGUGGGGCUGCAGGGCCAGGGUCCCUGAGAGUGGGCCAGCCUGGGCAGGUGCACGUCAGACAUGGACACUGGGGCCAGACAGGGAUCCAGGGACUGCAGCCAACUCCUGUUGAGAGUCAGCCCACCAUUCCACAGCCCCACCCUAAAGAUGUUGCAGAGAGCUGAGCCACCAGCUGGCUAUGGGCCUCUCACUACUCUACACCUCAGUUUCUCCAUCUGCCAGCCAGCUCUGAGACUCCCAGAGUGGAUGCUGGGCAGAUGAUUGGCAGAGUUGGUGGCCCCUGUCCCUGUGUGUUGAGACUCUGUGAGGCCCUGCAUGGAUAAGGGUCUCCGAUACACGGUGGAGGACGGGAGGAUGUGUGCUCACGAGUGUGCCUCUGGGAACAGUGGGCGCCGUGCCCUUGGGGUGCUGUUAGAGCACACGGGUUGAUGUGCUCGGCCUGUGCCGGGCUGGGUACUUGCACACGUGUAUGUACAUGCAUGUGUCCCUGUCUGAGGGGUCAUGUAUAUGCAUGUGUGUGUGCCUGGGCAUGUGUAGCAGGGGCCGGGCUUUCCUGUGAUCACUGGCUGACUCAUGCACCUGCCACCCGGGUGAAGUCAUCCCUCGUUUUUAGCUCCCUGAGGUCAUUUGCCAGCAGGGACUCUUGGGGCCUCUGGAUCCUACUGCGGGGCUGCUAGGCCGGGGCUGAUGGGUGGUGCCGCAGGGUUGCCAGGUCUUGCUGCGGGGGCGUGGCUCUCCUGGACCACCCCAGCUCUGCCUGUCAGACCCUCACCACAGCCUUGGUGGGAGGGAUAAGCUGGGCCACAGAGUGGCAUCGGGGUCCUGAGAUGUCCUCCCCUUUUCCUCUCCCGCUUACCCCCACUGCCUAGCUAGGGAAGAGGGGGUUUUUCUCUGAGUUUUUAAUAGAUGUAAAUAUAUACAUAUAUGAGGGGCUACAUCCCACUGGCAGAGUCCUGGGUAACGUUUCCUCAGUCUUGCUUUAUACCCUCCUCACUCUGUCGCCAGAACUGCAGCCCCUCAGUGCCUGGGCCCCUGCUUGAACUCAGAUGAGCCCCGCCCAGGGCCCAGCAGAGAGAGCUCAGGGCCUGACACACAUUUGCCAGAUACAGAUGGGGCAGCCCAGCCCCAGCAGUGAUGGGCCACACAAGCCUUCUCCUGCUUCAGAGCAGUCCCAGCUCCCCAGUGCCUUUGGAGAAGAGCCCAGCCUGCCCUGCCUGGCAGCGUGCCAGUUGUCCCCACUCUAGGCCUCAGUCUAUUUCUUUUUCCCAGGGAACAGGUCCCCUUUUCCUAGCCAGGUCCACAGCAGGCAUUCCACCUACAUCUCAAGACUGAGGGCGAGAUGAGGCCCAAAGCCUUCCUUGCCAGAUUGCCUUCUCUGGGGGUGCUUGAAAUCCCACUUGGACUGUGAAGUUCUAGGAGCAGAGCCCAGGCAGCCAGGCCUCACUGGCCACGAUGCCGGAGGCACCUGAUGUGCUGGAGGAGACCGUGACGGUGGAGGAGGACCCCGGCACACCCACUUCCCAUGUGUCUAUUGUCACAUCCGAAGAUGGCACAACCCGGCGCACCGAGACCAAGGUCACCAAGACUGUCAAGACGGUGACCACUCGGACAGUACGCCAGGUGCCCGUGGGCCCAGAUGGACUCCCCCUGCUGGAUGGCGGCCCCCCACUAGGCCCUUUUGCAGAUGGUGCCCUGGACCGGCAUUUCCUGCUGCGUGGUGGUGGCCCAGUGGCCACACUCUCUCGAGCCUACCUCAGCAGUGGGGGUGGCUUUCCCGAAGGCCCCGAGCCCCGGGACAGCCCCAGCUAUGGCAGCCUGUCCCGAGGGCUGGGCAUGCGGCCCCCACGUGCUGGCCCCCUUGGCCCAGGCCCUGGUGAUGGCUGCUUCACACUGCCUGGCCACCGGGAAGCCUUCCCGGUGGGUCCUGAGCCUGGGCCACCAGGUGGCCGCUCCCUGCCCGAGCGCUUCCAGGCAGAGCCGUAUGGCUUGGAGGAUGACACGCGCAGCCUGGCCGCUGAUGACGAGGGUGGCCCUGAGCUGGAGCCUGACUAUGGCACGGCCACAAGGAGGAGGCCUGAGUGUGGGCGGGGCCUUCAUACCAGGGCCUACGAGGACACAGCAGAUGAUGGCGGCGAGCUGGCGGACGAGCGGCCUGCGUUCCCAAUGGUGACGGCGCCCCUGGCCCAGCCUGAACGGGGCAGCAUGGGCAGCCUGGACCGGCUGGUGCGGCGCUCGCCCUCAGUGGAUAGCGCCCGCAAGGAGCCGCGCUGGCGGGACCCUGAGCUGCCUGAGGUGCUGGCCAUGCUGCGGCACCCCGUGGACCCCGUGAAGGCCAAUGCGGCCGCCUACCUGCAGCAUCUGUGCUUUGAGAACGAGGGUGUCAAGCGGCGUGUACGGCAGUUGCGGGGGCUGCCGCUGCUUGUGGCACUGCUGGACCACCCGCGGGCUGAGGUGCGGCGCCGGGCCUGUGGGGCACUGCGCAACCUCUCCUAUGGCCGCGACACUGACAACAAGGCCGCCAUCCGGGACUGCGGUGGUGUGCCUGCCCUGGUGCGCCUGCUGAGGGCUGCCCGGGACAACGAGGUCCGUGAGCUUGUCACUGGCACCCUGUGGAACCUGUCAUCCUAUGAGCCCCUGAAGAUGGUCAUCAUUGACCAUGGCCUGCAGACGCUGACCCACGAGGUGAUCGUGCCCCACUCAGGAUGGGAGCGUGAGCCCAACGAGGACUCCAAGCCACGGGACGCCGAGUGGACAACUGUCUUCAAGAACACGUCGGGCUGCCUGAGGAAUGUGAGCUCCGAUGGUGCUGAGGCCCGGCGGCGACUCCGGGAGUGUGAAGGGCUGGUGGACGCGCUCCUGCAUGCCCUGCAGUCGGCUGUGGGCCGGAAGGACACUGACAACAAGUCGGUGGAGAACUGCGUGUGCAUCAUGCGGAACCUGUCCUACCACGUGCACAAGGAGGUGCCCGGGGCCGACAGGUACCAGGAGGCCGAGCCCGGGCCCCUGGGCAGUGCUGUAGGCUCCCAGCGCCGGAGGCGGGAUGAUGCCAGCUGCUUUGGAGGCAAGAAGGCCAAAGAGGAGUGGUUCCACCAAGGAAAGAAGGAUGGUGAGAUGGACCGGAACUUUGACACGCUAGACCUGCCCAAGCGAACUGAGGCCGCCAAAGGCUUUGAGCUGCUGUACCAGCCCGAGGUGGUACGUCUCUACCUCUCCCUCCUCACGGAGAGCCGGAACUUCAACACCCUGGAGGCUGCCGCCGGCGCUCUGCAGAACCUCAGUGCCGGCAACUGGAUGUGGGCCACGUACAUCCGCGCCACAGUGCGCAAAGAGCGCGGGCUGCCGGUGCUUGUGGAACUGCUGCAGUCUGAGACCGACAAGGUGGUGCGCGCCGUCGCCAUCGCUCUGCGCAACCUCUCGCUGGACCGGCGCAACAAAGACCUCAUCGGGAGCUACGCCAUGGCUGAGCUUGUGCGGAAUGUGCGCAAUGCACAGGCUCCGCCGCGACCGGGGGCCUGCCUGGAGGAAGACACCGUGGUGGCGGUGCUCAACACCAUCCACGAAAUCGUGUCCGACAGCCUGGAUAACGCGCGCUCGCUCCUGCAGGCACGCGGGGUGCCAGCGUUGGUGGCUCUCGUGGCCUCCAGCCAAUCGGUACGCGAAGCGAAGGCGGCGUCACACGUGCUGCAGACAGUGUGGAGCUACAAGGAGCUGCGUGGUACCUUGCAGAAAGAUGGUUGGACCAAGGCGCGCUUCCAGUCAGCUGCUGCUACUGCCAAGGGGCCUAAGGGAGCACUGAGUCCUGGGGGCUUCGAUGACAGCACGCUGCCACUGGUGGACAAGAGCCUUGAGGGCGAGAAAACUGGCAGCCGGGAUGUGAUCCCCAUGGAUGCGCUGGGCCCAGACGGAUACUCCACGGUGGACCGGAGGGAGCGGAGGCCACGGGGCGCCAGCUCUGCAGGAGAGGCCUCUGAGAAGGAACCCUUGAAAGGAUACAGAAGACGUCAGCGGACUGAAAGACACCAGACCACUGCACCUGCACGAGUUAAACAGGAAAGAAGGAGGGAAGGGCAGAAAGGAGCAUGGGUCACCUUUGGAGGCUGCCAGGGGCCCACUCCUUUACGAAACUGGUCAAGAGGGGAAAGAAGGCAGCACCUGUCCUGCCUGUCGCCCGACACUGCAAGCCUCCUACCAGCUACUCAGACCACCUGGAGAACUGGCUAAACAUGCAUCAGCGUCUGAGCAGGACUGAAAAUCUAAUGCCGUGGAGAAGCGACAGUGUCAGAGGAGCAGGUGACACUAUGCUGAGGUGGUUUUCAUCUGGCCCACCCUCCUUAGACUCUCCUCCCUUCAAGAGUUGGAGCCUCACAGAGGUUGCAGGGAGCCAAGAUCGCGCCACUGCACUCCAGCCUGGGCGACAGAGCGAGAGACUGUCUCGAGAAACAACAACAAAAAGUUGGAGCCUCAGACCAAGCACACACCUGUACUCCCAGCACUUUGGGAGGUUGAGGCAAGAGGAUCGCUUGAGGCCAGGAGUUUGAGACCAGUCUGGGCAACAUAGGGAGACCCCAUUUCUACAAAAAAUUUUUAAAUUAGCCAGGUGUAGUGGUGCAUGCCUUUAGUCCUAGCUACUCAGGAGGCUGAGGUGGGAGGAUCACUGGAGCUCAGGAGUUUGAGGCUACAGUGAGCUAUGAUGUCAUCACUGCACUCCAGCCUGGGCACAGAGCAAGACUCUGUCUUUUUCUUUUUUUUUUUUUUUUUUUAAGGGGGAACUCAUUCCUCUUCCUUUGGGCAUGGGCUGGACUUGGUGACUACAGCAGCCCGGUGGAGAGGCCUCCUCAAAGCAGCCCUUGAUUUUGAAUUGCAACCUGCUCCUGAGCCCCUCACCCCUCGUGCCUCCGAUGCUCACAGAACCCACUGAGGGGAUGGCUAGACCCUCACAAGAGCCAGGUUGUCCCCUAACCCUCCACAAGGGGGCACAGGGCCCCAGCCCUGAGUGUGCAGAUGUGCGUUUAACAAGGACACCCAUUCCCAAUUCAUGACUUCCCACUUCAUGACUUUGCUUCUUUUGAGAUAAUUACCAGCUUUGCGCAAGCAGCACUGAGAAAACUAUUAGUUUCCUAGUUACUAAACUGCAAUGUUUGCUACUUUUCUAUGAAGGCAGGCCCCUGUAAUUAGCACCCACAUCACAGCUGCUGAAACUCGGCCGCAGUAACGCAGGCCCAGCUGUGGGUGUCUUUCCUGCCCAAGUGAAGCCCAUCUGGCUGAGUGCCAGCUCUCUGCCAUCAAUACCCAAUUGCCAGCAUCAUGCUCCUUUGUCAGGGGUGAGCCCCCCUCCAGCUACCCUGUCUUGGCCUGUAGGUCUCCCUCCCACCCUCCCAAUGCCCACCCCCUUGGCCACUACAGGUCCUCCCUCUCCACGGCCAGGGUUCAGUGCCUCCUCGUGAGUUCAGGGCAUCUGAAAUGCCCUCCCCACAGCCCUCUCCACACUCCACAAGGCUGACAGGGAUCUUUCCAGAAAAGUUUUUGUUGUUUUUUGUUGUUUUGAAAGCUGGAAUACGGCCGGACGCAGUGGCUCACGCCUGUAAUCCCAGCACUUUGGGAGGCCGAGGCGGGCGGAUCACGAAGUCAGGAUAUUGAGACCAUCCUGGCCAAUGUGGUGAAACCCCAUCUCUACUAAACUACAAAAAACUAGCCGGGUGUGGCAGCGCGCGCCUGUAGUCCCAGCUACUCAGGAGGCUAAGGCAGGGUAAUCGCUUGAACCCAAGAGGUGGAGGUUGCAGUGAGCCGUGAUCGUGCCACUGCACUCCAGCCUGGUGACAGAGCAAGACUCCAUCUAAAAUAUAUAUAUAUAUUUUUUCUUUUGCCAUGUUGCCCAGGCUGGUCUCGAACUCUCCUGGCCUCAAGCGCUCCUCCUGCCGUAGCCUCCCAAAGUGCAAGGGUUACAGGCAUGAGCCCCUGAGCCCAGCUCCAGAAGACAGGUCUAACCUCAUCCUCACCUGCCCAAAGUCCUGUGUGCCCUGACUCCCAUUGUUCCUGGAACAUUCUCUGCCCUUUCACACCUCA